AUGACGGGUAAAAUAUAAACGAGAAAACAAAAGAGACAAGGCUGGGCUUCCAGAAACAAGAUAAAUAUCUUCAUGGACCAGAAAUGCCAAGUAGUGAGCAAAACUGCAGCCUGGGCCUGCUGGACUCUCUAUCCAAGGCAGGUGGUGGUGUCCAGGAAUUUGGCUACAAGUAACAGAGACUAAAUGUGCACCAUGUGGGACAAGGGGCCAGAGCCAGAUUCACUUCUUGAAGCCAAGGACUAGGGUGGAACUUUUAUCCAGUUUUGGGAAGAAACUAAGAAAAAAUAUUGCCAGUCUUCUGCCAAGGGCUAUGGUUUUAUAGGAAGUUGUGAGCCUAGGGAUAACAAAGACAGCUUUGUGUCCAUCUGCUUGCUCAGUGACCAGAUAUGUGAUAUGCUCAGUAUACUUAUGAAACAGCUGCUCCAAGAAGUCAUCAUAAGACUUCUUCUAGACUUUUGGACUCAGGGGCCCUGGUAGAAGCAGAUGCAAAACUGCUAGACAGGGAAGGAUGUACACAGAGAGGGAGGGGAAAGGAAGUAAACAAACAUCCCAAAAGAAAAGGCUCCUGUUCAAAACUCUGAUAAAUUAAAAUUCCAAAAUCCAUAAAUCUAAUGCUAAGAAGGAUCACCAGCAAAAUCAACUAUUGGGAUAUAUAUAUAUAUUUAUUCCAGAUGAAAUAUAUAGCCUGACCAAGACUUUAUGUAUGUUUUGGAUACUCAAAAAGAUAAUCGAUGAGAUAACAUCCAUUGAAAAGGAACAAGAAAUCAUGAAACAAAAGCAGGCUGAAAUGAAGUAGGACAGUCGAUACAACUAAUCGGGAGUCUUGGGAAUGAAAAAUACAAUAAUUGAAACCAAAACUCAGCACACAGAAUUAAACUAUACACUGGACAUAGAUGAACAAAGAACUAGUGAACUGAAGAAGGUGAUGAGAACUUCAUCCAGCAAGCAGCACAGACAGAUUUUUUUUUUUUAAGUGGAAGAGCAGUUAAAAGCCAUGGUGAAUAGAUUGGGAAUUUCCAACAUCUGUCUAGUAGGAUUUCCAAAGAAGAAAAUGGAGGGAAUGGUAGAGAAACUGGAUUGCAAAGAAUUGAAGGAAAUCUCAAAUCCUCAGCUUAAAAGUGUGUCACAACUGCCAAGCAGGAUAAAGAAAGAUAAAUCUACUCUUCAUUACAUCAUGCCAUAACUGUGGGCAUUCAGAGAAAACCUAAAAGCCACUAAGGGAUAAGAAAGACAAAUAUACUGGGAAGGCACAGCAGUUUGACUGUUAGCAGAUUUCUAACAUAUCAACCAUUAAUACCAGAAGACAGUAGAGAAAUAUUAAAGUGCUGAAAGAAAAAUGACAUUCAAUCUAGAAUUUUAUACCGAGUUAAAUAUACUCAAGACUGUCGAUGAAAGAAAGACAUUUUUAUUUAAAGACCAGGAUAACUUACCACUCAGUGACCCUCAUUUUGAAAAAAACUACUCAAGGAUGUUCUUCAGGAGGAAGGAAAUUGAACCCAUAAGAAUGGAGUGGGAUACAGAAGGCAACGCUGAUGGAUUUACAACUGAGUGACAGUAACUUUCGUCGACACAUCCUGUUGCAGUAUCUCAUUUUAUUCCAAUAUCUCAAGGGGCAGGUCAAAUUCAAAAGUUCAAACUAUGUUUUAACUGAUGAGCAAUCACUUUGGAUUGAAGAUACUACAAAAUCAGUUUAUCAACUACUAUCUGAAAACCCCCCCGAUGGAGAAAGAUUUUCAAAGAUGGUAGAGCAUAUAUUAAACACUGAAGAAAACUGGAACUCGUGGAAAAAUGAAGGUUGCCCAAGUUUUGUGAAAGAAAGUGUAUGUUUUGUUCACGACAGAACAUCAGAUACCAAACCUACGAGAAUAAUUCGGAAGAGAACAGCACCCGAGGACUUCCUAGGGAAAGGACCCACCAAAAAAAUUCUGAUGGGAAAUGAGGAGUUAACAAGGCUUUGGAAUCUUUGCCCUGAUAAUAUGGAAGCCUGUAAAUCAGAGACAAGGGAACACAUGCCCACUUUGGAGGAAUUCUUUGAAGAAGCCAUUGAACAGGCAGACCCUGAAAAUAUGGUGGAAAAUGAAUAUAAGGCUGUGAACAAUUCAAAUUAUGGUUGGAGAGCCCUGAGACUAUUAGCACGGAGAAGCCCUCACUUCUUCCAGCCAACCAACCAGCAGUUUAAAAGUUUACCAGAAUAUCUUGAAAAUAUGGUAAUAAAGCUAGCCAAGGAAUUACCGCCUCCUUCUGAAGAAAUAAAAACAGGUGAGGAUGAAGAUGAGGAAGAUAAUGAUGCUCUACUGAAGGAAAAUGAAAGUCCUGAUGUUCGGCGAGACAAACCUGUAACAGGAGAACAAAUAGAGGUAUUUGCCAACAAGCUGGGUGAACAAUGGAAGAUUCUGGCUCCCUACUUGGAAAUGAAAGACUCAGAAAUUAGGCAGAUUGAGUGUGACAGUGAAGACAUGAAGAUGAGAGCUAAGCAGCUCCUGGUUGCCUGGCAAGAUCAAGAGGGAGUUCAUGCAACACCUGAGAAUCUGAUUAAUGCACUGAAUAAGUCUGGAUUAAGUGACCUUGCAGAAAGUCUAACUAAUGACAAUGAGACAAAUAGUUAGCUUCUUUUUUUUUUCUUUUUAUUAAAACUGUGAUAGAUUUUGUUACCAAGCAGCAUUUGAUAAGAGGUCCACUGGUUUUGGUAAACAAUAAACAUUUUUAUAACAA